GAGCUGGGCUGGCGGAGCAGAGGUGCAGAAGCAACUGAGUCCAAGUUGUCUGGCGGCUUCAGGUGGACCCAGAAGACGUCCCCAACUCAGGGAGAUUCAGCGAUCACUCACUCGCUGUACAGAAUGAUAUUCCUCACGGCACUGCCUCUGUUCUGGAUUAUGAUUUCAGCCUCCCGAGGGGGUCACUGGGGUGCCUGGAUGCCCUCGUCCAUCUCGGCCUUCGAAGGCACGUGCGUCUCCAUCCCCUGCCGCUUUGACUUCCCGGAUGAGCUGCGGCCCGCUGUGGUGCAUGGUGUCUGGUACUUCAAUAGCCCCUACCCCAAGAACUACCCCCCGGUGGUCUUCAAGUCGCGCACCCAAGUAGUCCACGAGAGCUUCCAGGGCCGCAGCCGCCUCCUGGGGGACCUGGGCCUGCGAAACUGCACCCUCCUGCUCAGCAACGUCAGCCCCGAGCUGGGCGGGAAGUACUACUUCCGUGGGGACCUGGGCGGCUACAACCAGUACACCUUCUCAGAGCACAGCGUCCUGGAUAUCGUCAACACCCCCAACAUCGUGGUGCCCCCAGAGGUGGUGGCAGGCACGGAGGUGGAGGUCAGCUGCAUGGUGCCGGACAACUGCCCAGAGCUGCGCCCUGAGCUGAGCUGGCUGGGCCACGAGGGGCUGGGGGAGCCCGCUGUGCUGGGCCGGCUGCGGGAGGACGAGGGCACCUGGGUGCAGGUGUCACUGCUGCACUUCGUGCCCACGAGGGAGGCCAACGGCCACAGGCUGGGCUGCCAGGCCUCCUUCCCCAACACCACCCUGCAGUUCGAGGGCUACGCCAGCAUGGACGUCAAGUACCCCCCGGUGAUUGUGGAGAUGAACUCCUCGGUGGAGGCCAUCGAGGGCUCCCACGUGAGCCUGCUCUGUGGGGCUGACAGCAACCCCCCGCCGCUGCUGACCUGGAUGCGGGACGGGACAGUCCUCCGGGAGGCGGUGGCCGAGAGCCUGCUCCUGGAGCUGGAGGAGGUGACCCCCGCCGAAGACGGCGUCUAUGCCUGCCUGGCCGAGAAUGCCUAUGGCCAGGACAACCGCACCGUGGGGCUCAGUGUCAUGUAUGCACCCUGGAAGCCAACAGUGAACGGGACAAUGGUGGCCGUAGAGGGGGAGACGGUCUCUAUCUUGUGCUCCACACAGAGCAACCCGGACCCUAUUCUCACCAUCUUCAAGGAGAAGCAGAUCCUGUCCACGGUCAUCUACGAGAGCGAGCUGCAGCUGGAGCUGCCGGCCGUGUCACCCGAGGAUGAUGGAGAGUACUGGUGUGUGGCUGAGAACCAGUAUGGCCAGAGGGCCACCGCCUUCAACCUGUCUGUGGAGUUCGCCCCUGUGCUCCUCCUGGAGUCCCACUGCGCGGCAGCCCGAGACACGGUGCAGUGCCUGUGCGUGGUGAAGUCCAACCCGGAGCCGUCCGUGGCCUUUGAGCUGCCAUCGCGCAAUGUGACCGUGAACGAGAGCGAGCGGGAGUUCGUGUACUCGGAGCGCAGCGGCCUCGUGCUCACCAGCAUCCUCACGCUGCGGGGGCAGGCCCAGGCCCCGCCCCGCGUCAUCUGCACCGCGAGGAACCUCUAUGGCGCCAAGAGCCUGGAGCUGCCCUUCCAGGGAGCCCAUCGACUGAUGUGGGCCAAGAUCGGGCCUGUGGGCGCCGUGGUCGCCUUUGCCAUCCUGAUUGCCAUCGUCUGCUACAUUACCCAGACACGCAGGAAAAAGAACGUGACAGAGAGCCCCAGCUUCUCGGCAGGGGACAACCCUCCCGUCCUGUUCAGCAGCGACUUCCGCAUCUCUGGGGCACCAGAGAAGUACGAGUCCAAAGAGGUUUCUACCCUGGAAUCUCACUGAGUGCCCCAGGAGAGCGAGAGGCGCCUGGGAUCUGAGAGGAGGCUGCUGGGCCUUCGGGGUGAGCCCCCAGAGCUGGACCUGAGCUAUUCUCACUCGGACCUGGGGAAACGGCCCACCAAGGACAGCUACACGCUGACGGAGGAGCUAGCUGAGUAUGCUGAAAUCCGGGUCAAGUGAAGGAGCUGGGGGCAGCCUGCGUGGCUGACCCCCCUCAGGACCCUCGCUGGCCCCCACUGGCUGUGGGCUCCCUUCCUCCCAAAAGUAUCGGGGGCUGGGGCAGGAGGGGAGUGAGGCAGGUGACAGUGAGGUCCUGGGGGCCUGACCUCCCCCUCCUUCCCAGCUGCCCCUCCCUGCCAGCACCCCCACGCCCUCAUUACGGCUCCUCUCUAACCUCCUUUACCCUCAUCUGUCUGGAGGGGAGCUCUGUCUGUCCGUGUUAUUUAUUGCUACUUCCUGCCUGGUCUCCUGCCCCCACACCUGGCCCUGGGGCCUGUACAAAAGGGACAUGAAAUAAAUGCCCCAAAGCCAAA